AGUUCUAAAGAGAGGCUGUUUACCAGAACAGCAUAACAAGGGCAGGUCUGACUGCAAGGCUGGGACUGGGAGGCAGAGCCGCCGCCAAGGGGGCCUCGGUUAAACACUGGUCGUUCAAUCACCUGCAAGACGAAGGAGGCAAGGAUGCUGUUGGCCUGGGUACAAGCAUUCCUCGUCAGCAACAUGCUCCUAGCAGAAGCCUAUGGAUCUGGAGGCUGUUUCUGGGACAACGGCCACCUGUACCGGGAGGACCAGACCUCCCCCGCGCCGGGCCUCCGCUGCCUCAACUGGCUGGACGCGCAGAGCGGGCUGGCCUCGGCCCCCGUGUCGGGGGCCGGCAAUCACAGUUACUGCCGAAACCCGGACGAGGACCCGCGCGGGCCCUGGUGCUACGUCAGUGGCGAGGCCGGCGUCCCUGAGAAACGGCCUUGCGAGGACCUGCGCUGUCCAGAGACCACCUCCCAGGCCCUGCCAGCCUUCACGACAGAAAUCCAGGAAGCGUCUGAAGGGCCAGGUGCAGAUGAGGUGCAGGUGUUCGCUCCUGCCAACGCCCUGCCCGCUCGGAGUGAGGCGGCAGCUGUGCAGCCAGUGAUUGGGAUCAGCCAGCGGGUGCGGAUGAACUCCAAGGAGAAAAAGGACCUGGGAACUCUGGGCUACGUGCUGGGCAUUACCAUGAUGGUGAUCAUCAUUGCCAUCGGAGCUGGCAUCAUCUUGGGCUACUCCUACAAGAGGGGGAAGGAUUUGAAAGAACAGCAUGAUCAGAAAGUAUGUGAGAGGGAGAUGCAGCGAAUCACUCUGCCCUUGUCUGCCUUCACCAACCCCACCUGUGAGAUUGUGGAUGAGAAGACUGUCGUGGUCCACACCAGCCAGACUCCAGUUGACCCUCAGGAGGGCACCACCCCCCUUAUGGGCCAGGCCGGGACUCCUGGGGCCUGAGCCCCCCCAGUGGGCAGGAGCCCAUGCAGACACUGGUGCAGGACAGCCCACCCUCCUACAGCUAGGAGGAACUACCACUUUGUGUUCUGGUUAAAACCCUACCACUCCCCCGCUUUUUUGGCGAAUCCUAGUAAGAGUGACAGAAGCAGGUGGCCCUGUGGGCUGAGGGUAAGGCUGGGUAGGGUCCUAACAGUGCUCCUUGUCCAUCCCUUGGAGCAGAUUUUGUCUGUGGAUGGAGACAGUGGCAGCUCCCACAGUGAUGCUGCUGCUAAGGGCUUCCAAACAUUGCCUGCACCCCUGGAACUGAACCAGGGAUAGACGGGGAGCUCCCCCAGGCUCCUCUGUGCUUUACUAAGAUGGCCUCAGUCUCCACUGUGGGCUUGAGUGGCAUACACUGUUAUUCAUGGUUAAGGUAAAGCAGGUCAAGGGAUGGCAUUGAAAAAAUAUAUUUAGUUUUUAAAAUAUUUGGGAUGGAACUCCCUACUGACCUCUGAGAACUGGAAACGAGUUUGUACAGAAGUCAGAACUUUGGGUUGGGAAUGAGAUCUAGGUUGUGGCUGCUGGUAUGCUUCAGCUUGCUGGCAAUGAUGUGCCUUGACAACCGUGGGCCAGGCCUGGGCCCAGGGACUCUUCCUGUUUCAUAAGGAAAGGAAGAAUUGCACUGAGCAUUCCACUUAGGAAGAGGAUAGAGAAGGAUCUGCUCCGCCUUUGGCCACAGGAGCAGAGGCAGACCUGGGAUGCCCCAGUUUCUCUUCAGGGAUGGAUAGUGACCUGUCUUCAUUUUGCACAGGUAAGAGAGUAGUUAGCUAACCUAUGGGAAUUAUACUGUGGGGCCUUGUGAGCUGCUUCUAAGAGGCUAACCUGGAAACUAAGCUCAGAGGCAAGGUAAUAAAGCACUUCAGGGCUUGCUCCCCAAGUGGGCCUGAUUUAGCAGGUGGUCCUGCGGGCGUCCAGGUCAGCACCUUCCUGUAGGGCACUGGGGCUAGGGUCACAGCCCCUAACUCAUAAAGCAAUCAAAGAACCAUUAGAAAGGGCUCAUUAAGCCUUUUGGACACAGGACCCCAGAGAGGAAAAAGUGACUUGCCCAAGGUCGUAAGCAAGCUACUGGCAUGGCAAGAGCCCAGCUUCCUGACGGAGCGCAACAUUUCUCCACUGCACUGUGCUAGCAGCUCAGCAGGGCCUCUAACCUGUGAUGUCACACUCAAGAGGCCUUGGCAGCUCCUAGCCAUAGAGCUUCCUUUCCAGAACCCUUCCACUGCCCAAUGUGGAGACGGGUUAGUGGGGCUUUCUAUGGAGCCAUCUGCUUUGGGGACCUAGACCUCAGGUGGUCUCUUGGUGUUAGUGAUGCUGGAGAAGAGAAUAUUACUGGUUUCUACUUUUCUAUAAAGGCAUUUCUCUAUAUACAUGUUUUAUAUACCUCAUUCUGACACCUGCAUAUAGUGUGGGAAAUUGCUCUGCAUUUGACUUAAUUAAAAAAAAAAAAA